AUCUAUGGGAGGAAGAGAAAGUGGAAUCUCUGUAUCAUCUUUCUUAGUCCCGAUGACUCAACUUUUUUUGCAUACAUUUUAAAUCCUCUCCUAACCAACCCAGCCAUCUCAGGAGGACCUUGAUGAGUCAGUGACAUCUGAAUAAACUCAUUUCCAGAUUAAAGAAGAGAGCAGUGGCCUCAGCUCAGUGAUUAAUUACAUGAACUCCUUACGUGGUAUUCGACCAAUAUAAGCCCAUUAAGAGAAAGGCUGGGUUCUUGUUGUGGCCUACUGAAGACUCUCUACUCUCAUCUCCUGAAGAGCAGUAAGAGAGACCAAUGACAUGGAGUGGCGGAACCAUAGUGGGAGAGUGAGUGAGUUUGUGUUGCUGGGCUUCCCUGCUCCUGCGCCACUACAGGUACUAUUGUUUGCCCUUUUGCUGCUGGCCUAUGUGUUGGUGCUGACUGAGAACACACUCAUCAUUAUGGCAAUUAGGAACCAUUCUACCCUCCACAAACCCAUGUACUUUUUUCUAGCUAAUAUGUCCUUUCUGGAGAUCUGGUAUGUCACUGUCACUAUUCCCAAGAUGCUUGCUGGCUUUGUUGGAUCCAAACAGGAUCAUGGACAGCUAAUCUCCUUUGAGGGAUGCAUGACACAGCUCUACUUUUUCCUUGGCUUGGGCUGCACUGAGUGUGUCCUUCUCGCUGUUAUGGCCUAUGAUCGCUAUAUGGCCAUCUGCUAUCCUCUCCACUACCCAGUCAUUGUCAGUGGCCGGCUGUGUGUGCAGAUGGCUGCUGGCUCUUGGGCUGGAGGUUUUGGCAUCUCCAUGGUCAAAGUUUUUCUUAUUUCUGGCCUCUCUUACUGUGGCCCCAACAUCAUCAACCACUUUUUCUGUGAUGUCUCUCCAUUGCUCAACCUCUCAUGCACUGAUAUGUCCACAGCAGAGCUUACAGAUUUCAUCCUGGCCAUUUUUAUUCUUCUAGGGCCACUCUCUGUCACUGGGGCCUCCUAUGUGGCCAUUACUGGUGCUGUGAUGCACAUUCCUUCGGCUGCUGGACGCUAUAAGGCCUUUUCCACCUGUGCCUCUCAUCUCACUGUUGUGAUAAUCUUCUAUGCAGCCAGUAUCUUCAUCUAUGCUCGGCCAAAGGCACUCUCAGCUUUUGACACCAACAAGUUGGUCUCUGUACUGUAUGCUGUCAUUGUACCAUUGCUCAAUCCCAUCAUUUACUGCCUGCGCAAUCAAGAGGUCAAGAGAGCCCUAUGCUGUACUCUGCACCUGUACCAGCACCAGGAUCCUGACCCCAAGAAAGCUAGCAGAAAUGUAUAGAAGGGAUGUGUGAAAUCUGAUAAAAUGCUAUUAAACUUGGGAUCAAUGUGUUCUAUGAAGUCCAGUGGAGUUCUUAGGGCCUAAAUUGGGGGCCAGAGUUUCAAAGGCAUCACUAUGGAACUAGGAAUACUUUCUUUAACUAGUCCAAGAGGAGAGAGAGGAAUAGGUUGCAAGCUAGAAAAUGGAUUUCUGCAGGACAGGGCCAUAAAAUACAGGAUAGAGCUGGGUCCACUAUUGUCUGUCCCUUUGUAAUUUGCAUAGACAAGGUUCCAAUCAAGGAAGCACAGGCUUCAUUACGGAAAAGCAACACAAGACUUUUUGAUAAGAUCUCUAUUAGGUAGCAGAGGCCCAGGAGAUAUCAUUCUAGCGUGUGUUACAAGGCAAGGAGAUAAGAAACUAGGAAUUUUUGUUUUGGGAACAUAUCACCUAUCAAAACAUAAUGGUUUCUAGGUUUAUUUUCAAAUUUACUGUGGUCAGUGUCCACAUUGAACUAGUGGCUGAGUGCAGUUGUUUCAUCAAUACUCUGUCUCCCUGAUUAGACUAUAAGCACCAUGGUGACAGGAUCAGAUUUUCUUUUACAUCCUUUUAUUACCAUGGGCAGGAACAGUAUCUAGUGCAUGAUGGCUAUGAAUAUGUAUAAUGAAUGAAUAUAGUUUGGAACCAUGUAGGCAAGGCAUGUGUGUCAUGCCUAUAUGUGGGGUUGGCAGGUGCAGGAAGUAAACCCCUCAUACUUUACUAGUAUGCAGAGAGAUACAAAUUGGCUCAGCCUUGCCAGAAAAAAAUUUUGAAAAUAUGUAUUACAAAUCCUAAAAAUAUUGCAACCAUUCUGAUUCGGAAAGAUUUGUGCAGAUAGACACUUUUACUUAUAAAUACAGAAACAAGGAAAGGAAAUAAGCAAAAUAUGCUCAACUUUCGCAAACAGGGCACUGGUCAAAUAAAUUGUAGCUCAUAUGUUACAUGGAAAACUAUGCAGAAAUUGAAAUAAAGUGAUCUAAAUAGAGUUAAUGAAAGAAAAAAUAUUUCUAACUUAAUAAAAAUAUUAUGUUAUAUAACAGUAUCAAAAAUAUCAGCCAUAUUUGCUUGUUUAAACAAGACUAGAAGGAAUAUGACUAAAAUGCUGGCUAGAUAAUGCUGGACUGCUUACACCUGUAAAUUGCAUUCUGUGGCUAAGCAUUGCCAUCAAUAUAUUUAUUUAAAUGCUUUUUUUCUUAGCCCAUAUUAUAUAUAACUUUAUUUAUCUGGACAGGGAGAUGGAUACAGGGUAUGUCAGUAUGAUUUUCAGAAAUUUAGCUCCCUACUGUCACCCGACAACCAGAACUCUGAAGACAGUGAAGAUUCUAUCUCCAGAUAUGGAUCCAACUGUUGCUCAAGAUGUGGGAUCUAACUUUAUUGCUGUAUGUUACUUAAUAAAAUUUACAAAAGGAUAUUACCAAGGAUAUCAUGCAUUAUUUGCUAGCCCAUACUUAUUAAAAGUUUUAAUAUAAUGUGCAUAUCUAUUUGUGCCUAAACAGUAUAAGUAUCUUGUUGUAAUAAUUUUUUAAAUGACUGGAUAUAAAGUUCAUCAAAAAUCUACUGUCGAAGUGUCCCCGUAGAAGAAGUUUCUGAAAUGGGGUUGUGAUCAGGGAUGGGAGAGUCCUCCUCUAGGCAUUGUUAUUACAACUCUUUUAUAAACUCUUUUAUAAGUUAACUCGAGUUAAUAGGAAGUAAAAGCAUAAUGUUGAAUUUCUUCAUUGUGCUUUUCUUUUAUUUUCCAAUGCUUUAAAACACCUCUAAUUCUGAUUUCAAGUAUUGGAAUAGGGUUUAGCACAGUAUUCCUCACAUACUCACCUUUCAAUAAACCACGAAUGAGUUUGAGUCCCAUGUACUAUGGUGAGAUUGACACCUCUCCAGACGGGGACUGAAUUUUUAGUGAACAUAUGACCCUCAGGACUCAUAUUGAAAUUGAGGUCACAAAACUUUGUAAACUUUUUCAUGUGAAGUAUUGAUUAUCAGAUUAAGUAUCCCCCAUCCUCCAUUUAUGUAACUGAUUUUUCCCAUAAACGUAGAUGUAGAACUUUAUUUUAUCCUUGUUCCAUUUGAUCCUGUUUGUUUUCGACCAUCUUUGUAAUCUGCCGGUCUUUCAAAGUAUUGCUUAGAUAAUAUAAGUCUUUUAUAAUUCCCCUUUGCUAAUACAGUAUCUGGAGAAGCUUCUAGUCUCUUGCAUCAGUACAAGAGGUGGGAGUACUGGAUCUACCCGGGUUAUUCAGAGUGGCCAGAGGCAACUAACAACUACAGGCAAGUGAGGAUUAAUAUAAAUGACUUCUGUGCUCCAGGUGUCUAGUGGUUUCCAAUGUUGAGUAAACUCCAGAUUUCUCAGUCUGCCUUUUAAGUUUCUUCACAGCACAUUCUUAAUUUUCCUUUUUGUCCUUAUUUUAAUUUUUUGUCCACUACAAACCUUGUACAGGUGAAUUCUAGAUUGUGAUUAACAAUUUUUAUUUGAGACUAAUAAGCCAGUGUAUUUCACUGUUUGCUAAAACAUCACAUUGACCAGGAUCAGGAAACAAAAAUCCUUCUUGAUAAACAGCAUUUUAAAAAUAACAAUUGUUCUGCAGCUCUGUAAACCCUAUUUCCCUUCAUUAAAAAACCCUUACAGUUAUGAACAAGUAAAGACUGAGAAAUAUCAGAUCAAAGCUUGUCAAAGAGACAAGAUACCUAUAUGGAGUACGGUAUAUUGGAUUGGACCCUGGAACAUAAAGUAAUACUAACAGAAAAGAUAAUAAAAUCUGAAUAAAAUGGCAAAAUCUGAAUAGUUUAACAGUGAUGUAUCAAUUUUGGUUUCUUAUUUUGACAAGUAUGUAUGCUAAUGAAGGAUGAAUAUAUUAGAAGAAACAAACUGAGAGAUGGGUGUGUGAAAAACUCUCUUUAGCAUCUUUGCAAUUUUUCUGUAAGCCUAAUAUUGUUCCAAAAUUUAGAAGUUUAUUUUAAAAAGAAACACGUUGUUAGUUUUUCC